CCGGCGGGAAGUGAGCCAGGGCUUGGCGCGGCGGCCGUGGUUGCGGCGCGGGAAGUUUGGAUCCUGGUUCCGUCCGCUAGGAGUCUGCGUGCGAGGAUUAUGGCUGCUGUUCCUCAAAAUAAUCUACAGGAGCAACUAGAACGUCACUCAGCCAGAACACUUAAUAAUAAAUUAAGUCUUUCAAAACCAAAAUUUUCAGGUUUCACUUUUAAAAAGAAAACAUCUUCAGAUAACAAUGUAUCUGUAACUAAUGUGUCAGUAGCAAAAACACCUGUAUUAAGAAAUAAAGAUGUUAAUGUUACCGAAGACUUUUCCUUCAGUGAACCUCUACCCAACACCACAAAUCAGCAAAGGGUCAAGGACUUCUUUAAAAAUGCUCCAGCAGGACAGGAAACACAGAGAGGUGGAUCAAAAUCAUUAUUGCCAGAUUUCUUGCAGACUCCGAAGGAAGUUGUAUGCACUACCCAAAACACACCAACUGUAAAGAAAUCCCGGGAUACUGCUCUCAAGAAAUUAGAAUUUAGUUCUUCACCAGAUUCUUUAAGUACCAUCAAUGAUUGGGAUGAUAUGGAUGACUUUGAUACUUCUGAGACUUCAAAAUCAUUUGUUACACCACCCCAAAGUCACUUUGUAAGAGUAAGCACUGCUCAGAAAUCAAAAAAGGGUAAGAGAAACUUUUUUAAAGCACAGCUUUAUACAACAAACACAGUAAAGACUGAUUUGCCUCCACCCUCCUCUGAAAGCGAGCAAAUAGAUUUGACUGAGGAACAGAAGGAUGACUCAGAAUGGUUAAGCAGCGAUGUGAUUUGCAUCGAUGAUGGCCCCAUUGCUGAAGUGCAUAUAAAUGAAGAUGCUCAGGAAAGUGACUCUCUGAAAACUCAUUUGGAAGAUGAAAGAGAUAAUAGCGAAAAGAAGAAGAAUUUGGAAGAAGCUGAAUUACAUUCAACUGAGAAAGUUCCAUGUAUUGAAUUUGAUGAUGAUGAUUAUGAUACGGAUUUUGUUCCACCUUCUCCAGAAGAAAUUAUUUCUGCUUCUUCUUCCUCUUCAAAAUGCCUUAGUACGUUAAAGGACCUUGACACCUCUGACAGAAAAGAGGAUGUUCUUAGCACAUCAAAAGAUCUUUUGUCAAAACCUGAGAAAAUGAGUAUGCAGGAGCUGAAUCCAGAAACCAGCACAGACUGUGACGGGUCUCACUGUGUUGCCCAGGCUGGUCUUGAACUCCUGGACUUAAGCAAUCCUCCUGCCUUGGCCUCCCCAAAGGGCUGGGAUUACAGUCAUGAGCCACCAUGCCUAGCCAAGACUUUUUUUUUUUUCCCUCAAAGAAAAAUAUUAACAACAUAAUUAUUUUAUAGCUAGACAGAUAAGUUUACAGCAGCAGCUUAUUCAUGUGAUGGAGCACAUCUGUAAAUUAAUUGAUACUAUUCCUGAUGAUAAACUGAAACUUUUGGAUUGUGGGAACGAACUGCUUCAGCAGCGGAACAUAAGAAGGAAACUUCUAACGGAAGUAGAUUUUAAUAAAAGUGAUGCCAGUCUUCUUGGCUCAUUGUGGAGAUACAGGCCUGAUUCACUUGAUGGCCCUAUGGAGGGUGAUUCCUGCCCUACAGGGAAUUCUAUGAAGGAGUUAAAUUUUUCACACCUUCCCUCAAAUUCUGUUUCUCCUGGGGACUGUUUACUGACUACCACCCUAGGAAAGACAGGAUUCUCUGCCACCAGGAAGAAUCUUUUUGAAAGGCCUUUAUUCAAUACCCAUUUACAGAAGUCCUUUGUAAGUAGCAACUGGGCUGAAACACCAAGACUAGGAAAAAAAAAUGAAAGCUCUUAUUUCCCAGGAAAUGUUCUCACAAGCACUGCUGUGAAAGAUCAGAAUAAACAUACUGCUUCAAUAAAUGACUUAGAAAGAGAAACCCAACCUUCCUAUGAUAUUGAUAAUUUUGACAUAGAUGACUUUGAUGAUGAUGAUGACUGGGAAGACAUAAUGCAUAAUUUAGCAGCCAGCAAAUCUUCCACAGCUGCCUAUCAACCCAUCAAGGAAGGUCGGCCAAUUAAAUCAGUAUCAGAAAGACUUUCCUCAGCCAAGACAGACUGUCUUCCAGUGUCAUCUACUGCUCAAAAUAUAAACUUCUCAGAGUCAAUUCAGAAUUAUACUGACAAGUCAGCACAAAAUUUAGCAUCCAGAAAUCUGAAACAUGAGCGUUUCCAAAGUCUUAGUUUUCCUCAUACAAAGGAAAUGAUGAAGAUUUUUCAUAAAAAAUUUGGCCUGCAUAAUUUUAGAACUAAUCAGCUAGAGGCGAUCAAUGCUGCACUGCUUGGUGAAGACUGUUUUAUCCUGAUGCCGACUGGAGGUGGUAAGAGUUUGUGUUACCAGCUCCCUGCCUGUGUUUCUCCUGGGGUCACUGUUGUCAUUUCUCCCUUGAGAUCACUUAUCGUAGAUCAAGUCCAAAAGCUGACUUCCUUGGAUAUUCCAGCUACAUAUCUGACAGGUGAUAAGACUGACUCAGAAGCUACAAAUAUUUACCUCCAGUUAUCAAAAAAAGACCCAAUCAUAAAACUUCUAUAUGUCACUCCAGAAAAGAUCUGUGCAAGUAACAGACUCAUUUCUACUCUGGAGAAUCUCUAUGAGAGGAAGCUCUUGGCACGUUUUGUUAUUGAUGAAGCACAUUGUGUCAGUCAGUGGGGACAUGAUUUUCGUCAAGAUUACAAAAGAAUGAAUAUGCUUCGCCAGAAGUUUCCUUCUGUUCCGGUGAUGGCUCUUACGGCCACAGCUAAUCCCAGGGUACAGAAGGACAUCCUGACUCAGCUGAAGAUUCUCAGACCUCAGGUGUUUAGCAUGAGCUUUAACAGACAUAAUCUGAAAUACUAUGUAUUACCGAAAAAGCCUAAAAAGGUGGCAUUUGAUUGCCUAGAAUGGAUCAGAAAGCACCACCCAUAUGAUUCAGGGAUAAUUUACUGCCUCUCCAGGCGAGAAUGUGACACCAUGGCUGACACGUUACAGAGAGAUGGGCUCGCUGCUCUUGCUUACCAUGCUGGCCUCAGUGAUUCUGCCAGAGAUGAAGUGCAGCAGAAGUGGAUUAAUCAGGAUGGCUGUCAGGUUAUCUGUGCUACAAUUGCAUUUGGAAUGGGGAUUGACAAACCGGACGUGCGAUUUGUGAUUCAUGCAUCUCUCCCUAAAUCUGUGGAGGGUUACUACCAAGAAUCUGGCAGAGCUGGAAGAGAUGGGGAAAUAUCUCACUGCCUGCUUUUCUAUACCUAUCAUGAUGUGACCAGACUGAAAAGACUUAUAAUGAUGGAAAAAGAUGGAAACCAUCAUACAAGAGAAACUCACUUCAAUAAUUUGUAUAGCAUGGUACAUUACUGUGAAAAUAUAACGGAAUGCAGGAGAAUACAGCUUUUGGCCUACUUUGGUGAAAAUGGAUUUAAUCCUGAUUUUUGUAAGAAACACCCAGAUGUUUCUUGUGAUAAUUGCUGUAAAACAAAGGAUUAUAAAACAAGAGAUGUGACUGACGAUGUGAAAAGUAUUGUAAGAUUUGUUCAAGAACAUAGUUCAUCACAAGGAAUGAGAAAUAUAAAACAUGUAGGUCCUUCUGGAAGAUUUACUAUGAAUAUGCUGGUCGACAUUUUCUUGGGGAGUAAGAGUGCAAAAAUCCAGUCAGGUAUAUUUGGAAAAGGAUCUGCUUAUUCACGACACAAUGCCGAAAGACUUUUUAAAAAGCUGAUACUUGACAAGAUUUUGGAUGAAGACUUAUAUAUCAAUGCCAAUGACCAGGCGAUCGCUUAUGUGAUGCUCGGAAAUAAAGCCCAAACUGUACUAAAUGGCAAUUUAAAGGUAGACUUUAUGGAAACAGAAAAUUCCAGCAGUGUGAAAAAACAAAAAGCGUUAGUAGCAAAAGUGUCUCAGAGGGAAGAGAUGGUUAAAAAAUGUCUUGGAGAACUUACAGAAGUCUGCAAAUCUCUGGGGAAAGUUUUUGGUGUCCAUUACUUCAAUAUUUUUAAUACCGUCACUCUCAAGAAGCUUGCAGAAUCUUUAUCUUCUGAUCCUGAGGUUUUGCUUCAAAUUGAUGGUGUUACUGAAGACAAACUGGAAAAAUAUGGUGCGGAAGUGAUUUCAGUAUUACAGAAAUACUCUGAAUGGACAUCGCCAGCUGAAGACAGUUCCCCAGGGAUAAGCCUGUCCAGCAGCAGAGGCCCCGGAAGAAGUGCCGCUGAGGAGCUCGACGAGGAAAUACCCGUAUCUUCCCACUACUUUGCAAGUAAAACCAGAAAUGAAAGGAAGAGGAAAAAGAUGCCAGCCUCCCAAAGGUCUAAGAGGAGAAAAACUGCUUCCAGUGGUUCCAAGGCAAAGGGGGGGUCUGCCACAUGUAGAAAGAUAUCUUCCAAAACGAAAUCCUCCAGCAUCAUUGGAUCCAGUUCAGCCUCACAUACUUCUCAAGCGACAUCAGGAGCCAAUAGCAAAUUGGGGAUUAUGGCUCCACCGAAGCCUAUAAAUAGACCGUUUCUUAAGCCUUCAUAUGCAUUCUCAUAACAACCGAAUCUCAAUGUACAUAGACCCUCUUUCUUGUUUGUCAGCAUCUGACCAUCUGUGACUAUAAAGCUGUUAUUCUUGUUAUACCAUUUGAAGUUUUUACUCGUCUCUAUUAAUAUUUAAAUAAAUGCUGGGGGGUGAUAGUUCUUCUUUUUAAAAUAAACAUUUUCUUUUGAAUAAGCAUGUUUUGCUGCCGCUGCAAGUGUUGUGGCCGUUGUUUCUCAGAACGUCUGAGGCAGCAGCUGAAUCAUCUCAGUGCAAGAGCUUCUGAGCAUAACACGAAACCCAGAAGCCAAAGGAAGAGCCACGCGUGGGCCCUUGUGAAACUAAAGCUUUUCGUGUAAGACAACACAAACAAAAUUUAAAGACAAAUGACGGGGAAAAGAGGAGAAAAUAUAUUACAAAGGAUUAGUAUCCAUCAUACCAAAUACCCGUGAACCAGUCAGAAACAUCCCAGGGGGCAGGUGGACCAAGGAUGUGAACAGGCUAGUCUCAGAAGAAGAAAUACACAUGCUCAUGGCCCGGCACUGUGGCUCACGCCUGGGAUCCCAGCACUUUGGGAGGCCGAGGCAGGUGGAUCACGAGGUCAGGAGUUUGAGACCAGCCUGCCCAACAUGGUGAAACCCCGUCUCUACUAAAAAUACAAAAAUUAGCCAGGCGUGGUGUACAGGCACGCCUGUAGUCCCAGCUACUCAGGAGGCUGAGGCAAGAGAAUCGCUUGAACCCAGGAGGCGGAGGUUGCAGUGAGCCGAGAUCGUGCCACUGCACUCCAGCCUGGGUGACAGAGCAAGACUCCGUCUCAAAAAAAAAAAAAAAAAAAGAAAUAUACAUGCUCUGCAAAUAUGUGAAAAAGGUCAAUCUCCAUGAAUAAAAAUAUGAUAAAACCA